GGAGUUGGGGAAGCUGGGUUGGCUGGGUUGGUAGCUCCUACCUACUGUGUGGCAAGAAGGUAUGGGUCAUGAACAGAACCAAGGAGCUGCGCUGCUACAGAUGUUACCACUUCUGUGGCUGCUACCCCACUCCUGGGCCGUCCCUGAAGCUCCUACUCCAAUGUGGCCAGAUGACCUGCAAAACCACACAUUCCUGCACACAGUGUACUGCCAGGAUGGGAGUCCCAGUGUGGGACUCUCUGAGGCCUACGACGAGGACCAGCUUUUCUUCUUCGACUUUUCCCAGAACACUCGGGUGCCUCGCCUGCCCGAAUUUGCUGACUGGGCUCAGGAACAGGGAGAUGCUCCUGCCAUUUUAUUUGACAAAGAGUUCUGCGAGUGGAUGAUCCAGCAAAUAGGGCCAAAACUUGAUGGGAAAAUCCCGGUGUCCAGAGGGUUUCCUAUCGCUGAAGUGUUCACGCUGAAGCCCCUGGAGUUUGGCAAGCCCAACACUUUGGUCUGUUUUGUCAGUAAUCUCUUCCCACCCAUGCUGACAGUGAACUGGCAGCAUCAUUCCGUCCCUGUGGAAGGAUUUGGGCCUACUUUUGUCUCAGCUGUCGAUGGACUCAGCUUCCAGGCCUUUUCUUACUUAAACUUCACACCAGAACCUUCUGACAUUUUCUCCUGCAUUGUGACUCACGAAAUUGACCGCUACACAGCAAUUGCCUAUUGGGUACCCCGGAACGCACUGCCCUCAGAUCUGCUGGAGAAUGUGCUGUGUGGCGUGGCCUUUGGCCUGGGUGUGCUGGGCAUCAUCGUGGGCAUUGUUCUCAUCAUCUACUUCCGGAAGCCUUGCUCAGGUGACUGAUUCUUCCAGACCAGAGUUUGAUGCCAGCAGCUUCGGCCAUCCAAACAGAGGAUGCUCAGAUUUCUCACAUCCUGCCCAGGAUCUCCUCUUAGGGUAGAAGAAGUCUCUGGGACAUCCCUGGGGUGUGUGUGUAGAUUUCCCACCUGGGGACUCUGCUGUCCCUGGGCUUGCAUCCCAGGGAUCCCAGAGUGGCCUGCCUAUCACAACCACAUCCCUUCCCCCCACAAGGCAAUAAAUCUCAUUUCUUUA